GGGGUCCUCGUGGCCAGCCAAGAUGGCUGCCCCCGCAGUGAAGGUUGCCCGAGGAUGGUCGGGCCUGGCGUUGGGCGUGCGGCGGGCUGUCUUGCAGCUUCCAGGGCUAACUCAGGUGAGAUGGAGCCGCUAUAGUCCUGAAUUCAAGGAUCCCUUGAUUGACAAGGAAUAUUAUCGCAAGCCAGUGGAGGAGCUAACUGAGGAGGAGAAAUAUGUUCGGGAGCUCAAGAAGACUCAGCUCAUCAAAGCUGCUCCAGCAGGGAAAACAAGUUCUGUGUUUGAAGACCCAGUCAUCAGUAAAUUCACCAACAUGAUGAUGAUAGGAGGAAACAAAGUACUGGCCAGAUCCCUCAUGAUUCAGACUCUGGAAGCUGUGAAAAGGAAGCAGUUUGAGAAGUACCAUGCCGCUUCUGCAGAGGAACAGGCAACCAUCGAACGCAACCCCUACACCAUCUUCCAUCAAGCACUGAAAAACUGUGAGCCUAUGAUUGGGCUGGUACCCAUCCUCAAGGGAGGCCGUUUCUACCAGGUCCCUGUACCCCUACCCGACCGGCGUCGCCGCUUCCUAGCCAUGAAGUGGAUGAUCACUGAGUGCCGGGAUAAAAAGCACCAGCGGACACUGAUGCCGGAGAAGCUGUCACACAAGCUGCUGGAGGCUUUCCAUAACCAGGGCCCCGUGAUCAAGAGGAAGCAUGACUUGCACAAGAUGGCAGAGGCCAACCGUGCCCUGGCCCACUACCGCUGGUGGUAGAGUCUCCAGGAGGAGCCCAGGGCCCUCUGCCGCAAGAAACAGUGUGAGCUACUGCCACGCUGAAAACUACCUGUGGGUUAAGGAUGUAGUUCCUUUGUAAGGGUGGGCAGGCCUCGUAAGAAAGAUGUAGCAGCAUAUUCACUAUCCGUUAAUCCUUCUUUCUUUGAGGCUGGAACUUGCUCUCUCUGCCCCUAUUUCCUUGUAAAGAGGGAGCACAUUGACUUGGGAAUUUCCUCCAGGAAACUCAGGGCUGUUUUCUCUUCCCUUAGGUUGGGGCGGACCUUUGGAUAUAUAAAGGAAGCAGUUUUAGUAUCAGAAAAGAUUUAUUAGAAAAUUCUCACGCUGAACUGGUGUAGCAUGUGGUGCAGCAUUCAGUGAAACUGGCUGGAGGAAAUAGGCUUGUUUCCAGAGUUGUCCUUAUACAAAAUGUAUAAAAAGCAGUUUCUGGUGUGA